ACCUGCUGGGAGCUGGAGGAGGCGCGGAGCGAAGCCGGCCCUGCCAGCCACGCGGAGAAGCAGAGGCAGGUGAGCGCGAUGCAGCCGGCGCCGGGUCUGGGGCUCGGGGACUCCUCCCUGCACCGCUACCUGGACGGCGACUUCUGGAGCCUCAAGAACGAGCUGCGCGGACUCCUCGGCGGCGCCCGCUCUUCCGGCAAAGGUAUGAUUUAAGCUUGGAUGAAAUGAGAGCUUUGACAGUUCAGAGAGUGAAGUUUGCCAUGGACCUGCCUCUGUUAAAACGUGCAGGUCAGGAUCUGGCAGAGAAAACAAAGAAUUUUGUCAGCCGAAGCCUUGUCAUAGGAGAAGUCCUCUCCAUGGCGGACAUGGCCACAGGAGUGAAGUGCGGAAUAAUUUAUUGGCUAUUUGGUGGUGCUAUCAGGAAUCUCGGAAGCCCUGAACAUGUUACUAAGUGGUUUCAGCCACUCCAGGAGCAGAAAUACACUGGGAUGUUUGCAAUGACCGAGAGGGGCCAUGGGAGCAACGCGAGAGGGAUCCAGACCGAAGCCACCUUUGACCUCUCUGCCCAGGAGUUUGUAAUUGACACGCCGUGUGAAAAUGCGGAGAAGAUGUAUAUUGGAAAUGCCAUGUACGGGAAUUAUGCAGCUGUCUUUGCCCAGCUCAUCAUAGAUGGAAGAUCUCAAGGGCCCCACUGUUUCAUCGUUCCUGUCCGGGAUGAAAACGGAAGCUUGUACCCAGGAGUCACAGCUAUUGAUAUGAUGUACAAGGAGGGUCUGCAUGGUGUGGACAAUGGGAUAUUAAUAUUUGACAAGGUUCGGAUACCCAGGGAGAACCUGCUGGAUAAGUUUGGUUCCGUGGCUCCAGAUGGACAGUACCAUUCGCCUAUUAGGAACAAGAGUGCAAGAUUCAAUGCCAUGCUGGCAGCACUGACCCCUUCGAGAUUAGCUGUGGCUUUCCAAGCUAUGGGUGCCAUGAAGCUUGGGUUGACGAUAGCCAUUCGCUAUAGCCACAGCCGGAGGCAGUUUGGGCCCAAAACCAAGGAAGAGGUGAAGAUCAUUGAGCACCAAACACAGACCCUGCGGCUGAUGCCCCACCUGGCCACAGCCUUGGCCCUGACCUUCGUCAGCAGGUAUGCUGGGGCCCUCCUGGAUGAGGAUGUCUUCCAGGGAAAGGAGCUGGUCAACAGUCGCUCGCUGCAGGCUCUGGUGGCGGGGCUGAAGGCCUACAGCACCUGGGAGAACAUCCGCUGCCUGCAGGACUGCCGCGAGUGCACUGGAGGCAUGGGUUACAUGAUGGAAAAUCGAAUCUCAGGCUUAAAGUGUGACACAGAUGUGUUUGCCACUUUUGAAGGUGACGAUGUUGUUAUGCUUCAGGUUGUGGGGCGGGAACUGCUGGCCCAAUACACCAAACAGUAUGAAGAAAAACCACUCUUUGGCCUGCUCCAAAACUGGGCUGAAUCUGUGGGGGACAAGCUGAGAACCAGUUUCCUGGCAUUUAACAUGGACACAGUUGAUGAUCUCGCCUUUCUGUUGAAAGCAGUGAAAUUUCGUGAAAGGGUUCUUCAGCGGGGUUUGGUGGCCAGAAUUUAUUAUAAGGUAAAGACCAAGAAGGAGGAUUUUUUCCAUGCCUGGAACUCGUGUCUGCACCACGUGGCUUCUCUGUCCCUGGCACACACUCACCGAGAGUUUCUGUGAGGAUUAAAUGAAAUAACAUGGGUGGAAGCCCUAGGACCGUAUGGAGCAAAGGGAGCCAACAUUCAGUGAGGGCUCAGCCUAUCAGGCCCUGUGCAAAAUAUUAGGGACAGAGCAACUCUAAUCCCCCACUAGGCAGUGAGGAAGGAACCACUGCCUUCUCAACUUUCAUCUGAGGAAACCGAGGCACAGAGAGGUUAAUGAGUUGUCUAAGGUCACACAGUUAAAAGAGGCAGAAGGAAGACUCAAAUCCCAGCAGGCUGCUACCAUCUGCCCAUGUUGCAGGGCUCCCAGUGCUCGUUGGAGCUGAAUCUGGGAGCUCAGCAUUUCUAAAGAAGCAAAAUAAAAUAAAAAAUAAAAUAAGCCCUUCCCACUUUUUAAAUGUGUUUCCCACUUUUUAAAUGUGUUUUCGCUCCUUUGUUUCCCACUCUGUGAUCAAAAAAUUGUACAUUGUAUGAUGGACUGCAGAGAUCUGGUCUACAGCCCCUGUUCAUUUAACUUCUAAUAUCUAAGUAGUUUCAAAAUAUGGUUACAUUAGUACCAAAAUUGAUGGGCAAAAGUAACACCAAAAGUAAAAAAAGAAAUUAUUUGCACCAAGUAUACUGUAUUUGUGAGUUUUCCACUGGGAACAGGAUGGAGAAUAAGACCUUCCAAACGGUGAAUAAAAAUAAAAGUAUAGGAACUCUUGAUUUAUCAUACACACUCUAGAUAUAAUUUUGUAUUUAAAAAUAUUAUUCCAUACCACAUAUUGUAAAGUUAAAUAUGUUUGCAGUAAACAUACAUUUAAAUUUAGGUUUUAAAGGACAUGUUCUAAUCUCACAAAACAUUUAGCAAAUAACCUUUGAGCUCACAUGAGCCACCCACACAAAAACCAAAAUGAACUAUAGAAAAAAAACAUAGAAAAAGCAACUGUCUGUUGACAACCAGAUUUUCUUUCAGCUCUUUGAGUUUUUCUUCUAUAAAUAAUCUGUAUGUUUCAAAUGUGGCCAUCUUCUUUAAAGGUGCCUCCUGGCAUGUUCUCAUUUCAGUGUGUCUUAAAAACAAGAAUUAAAUGUGUAAAUCAUGGAAACUAUUGAGUUUUUGGAGGGGAGAUCUUUAAGAUACAUGCUUUUUAGAAACCAAAAGUGUCAAAAUGAAGCAUUAAGAUGAUGUAUUAUUUCUUCAAUGCAUCUGUUUAUCUUUUGUGAAAUCUCAAGUUUGAUAAAUCACCAGAGAUAAAAACAUCAUUUUUAACCUAUCAGAGAUCACAAGUGCCAGGAGGAAAAAUAGUGCUUUGUCUCCUCUUUAUGAAUUUACCUCUCUCUUUGCUUAUGACUUAUGAGAUUUUAUUUGCAGAGAAAACAUAAUGCUCUAUUAACUUGAAAAUGAUGGCUUUUACUCGAAACAUGAGAACCAAAAAGAAAAAAAAAAAGGCAGCGUUUAUCCUCUGAGAUACAAUCGUUUAACAAGUUUUGAUAUCUACUUAAAGUGGCACAGAAUGUUAGAGGGGGAAUAUGUUAACAAGGUAAUUAAAAGUGAGGUUUUCACCAGUAUUUCACCUUUGUCUACUGACACGUAGAAUCUCAGCUCUGGCUUAUCAAAGCAGAUAUUGAAUACUUUUGAAUUUUUAUAUAACAUUAGUGUAAGUAGAGAUUGCUGGCCCCUAUCUCUUGUGAUUCUUUUUUGCCCCUGAAAAUCACUCAGAAGUUCUCCCUUCAUUGGCCACCUGGAAAAUAAGAUAAUUCUCGUAGAUUUUUAUAACUAUGGGUGAAAAUUCUUCUGUGUCCAGGAGUGCAGCAACAAAGGACUUUGCAGUAGAGCUGGCUUCUAACCAGUUCUUUCUGUGAGCUAGAAGAUUAAAGUGCACGAAUCAUGCAAGUAGGUUAGUCUGGAAAACAUAACACAGCAGAAAAAAAUGGCUUUCAAAAAUGUUCAGAACAGCUGUUUCUCAGUAUGUAAACCAGCCUCUUGGUGCAGUGGAUAUCAGAGUUCCUUGCCUUGUGCAUAUUUUAUCAUUCUUCGAUCCUGAGCAGUUUAAGACAAAAUAAAUUUUAUGCAAACCCAUUCCAGGCCAUGGGCAUGCAGUUGAGUUUUUCUAGCAAUUGUGCUAUUUUAAGGAGACACCCAGGUUCUGCCCUAACACCAGAGGUGCCUAAGGUCGCAGCUGCUCAGGACCUGUGGCAGCUGUGAGCAGCUGAGCUCAGUUUGCUCUGUUCUUUCUUCUUGCAAGAAUCACACAGACCAUGUUGGUCCUAUGGAAUAGAAUCACAAUAUUGCCUCAGACCAUAGGACCAAUACAGCAGAAGGUCCUGAGAAGCUGCGGCUUGCUCCAUCUCUCAGCCUCCUACUGCUGCAUGAAAAAUAAACCUUGUAACUAUGGAGCUGCCCCUCCUGAAUCUGACAUCUACUCAGUUAUCCUUCGGAAACAAUCCUGAUGUGGAGCACCCUUCCUCAUUCCCUUAUCCACCCUUCUCGCCCCAUAUUUGUUGAAGUCCUGCCUUGUGCCAAGGACUGUGUUACACUCCAGGAAUAAAAGGUCCAGUAUGAAACAGCCCCUGCUCCCAAGGAGCACUGGUGAGAACUGAGAUGAGAGCCCCCAUAGACUAGGAGCCCUGAGAGAACACGGAAGAGACACAAGCUGGGCAGGGGGUGCAGGGUCCACGCGGCUCCCCACGAAGUUCCAGUGAGGCAAGCAGCAUUUGAGACUUUGCCUUUUGAAGGGCAGGUAGAAUUUAGCUAUCUGGAAGGUGGAAAGGACAUUCCGAGCAGAUGGAAGAACCAGGAGGGAGGCAUGAAGUGCGUGGAUGACUUGGGAAAGUGCUUGUGGCUUGGUGUGGUCGGGGUGUAGGGCCAAUGUGAGGGUGAACAGCAGGGUCCCACAGGGCCUGAGUGCCAAGGCCCGUAGCUGUCAUUGUCAACUCCCACUGUCAGUGGGGAGUCUUGGAAAAAGCUUUGGGAAGAUUUCUUCAGGUGUGGAGGUGAACAGCUCUGAGGACAGGAACUGAGGAGCAACAGCAGCAGGCCUGCGUGGAGGGGUGGGUUCUGGAGGUGCGAGGGCAAAGGGGCCUGGAGGGCCUCCAGGUGGAGGGUGAGCUAUGAGGAAAAGCCAAGGGCUUCUUCUGGGCACCAAGGUGGAGAGGAGAGAACUGGGUCCAACUCAGCUUGGACGUGUGGCGCAUGCAUGACCUGGGGCCACACAUGCAGAUGCCGAGACAGGCGCGUGGCAGAGAGGACUGCAGGGCCUCGUAACAUCCAGGUCCUGAGCCUGAGCACUAUAUUAAAUGGGAGGGCGAAUCGCUGCAAGGUGGAAAACAGGAUCAAUGCCACGCAUGAGGCAAUUGCAGCUGUCCUAUCCAUUAUCUUCCCAAUUUAAGUGUGACACUGGAGUCCACAGUGUUUGUUUCCCAAAAUUGGCUGACUCUUGUUCCGCUGAUGGGACAGUGGUGGUUGUGAUGGCCUCCAGCUGAGCGUUAGUGUCAAAGUUGUCCUUCCAUGCAGGUGAAGGGGGAUCUGCAGGUGGGACAGAGCCGGGCCAUGGGGAGGCUCACACUGGCUGCUGGAGAUGACACUGGGGAAAAGAUGUGGUGACAGUGGCUGCCGCCUCUGGCUGCCCCCGGCUCUACACCUUGCUCUUGGCUAAGACUGGAGCAGGCCCCAGGAAGCAGCCUUUGGCCAUGGUGAGCCAAGGCCAUGUCAAAUAGGGGACAGCGUGCCACUGUCCACCUGGGGGAGGGCAGCCCCCUGCACACAGGGAGUCCGUGGGCUCCAGAAGGGGUCCAGAUGAGCUGUGCCGUCAUCUCUUCCUGAGUGAAUGGUGCAUUUGCCCCAAGCUGAAAGGGCUCUGCCAUUCAGGAAAGCAGGUGACCACUGUGCUCUGUCUCCCGACUUUGUGCCUGAGCCAAAGACUACAGAUUGUUCCCUUAGCAACCAGCAGAGAGCCCUAAGAAGGAGGAUGAAUGUCUCGGGUUUGCAAUGCCCCCCAUGUGGAGAGAGGGCAGCUGCUUUUCUCCCUGAGCCCAGAACACGGCAGGCAGGUUGGGCUCCUUCAGGCCCCCCAGCCCCUUUGGGAACUGCUCACAUCUAGGAUUUUGCAACCAGUUCUCCACAUUUCACUCCCAUGGUGCAGUCUAGAAUAAAGACUUCUAAGAUGUCAGUCAGCCCCCAUUACGUUCCCAUCCCUGGGACUGGCCAAACUGGCAUUUUGCCUGCCUAGGGAAAUACAGUCUUAGUCUUAGUCUUAGUAUAGACUCACUUAGUUUAUUUGCUUAGAAGGUUUUCAGUACCUCCUAUUUGCCAGACUUAGGACUCAGAUUAUCAGAACAAUGUGACGCUUUUCAAUCCAGCAGAGGGAAUAGGAUGUGAACACAGCGCCCACACACACAUGGAGCAGGAGAGCCUGUGAGAGGUGCAGGCUCCCUGCACGGCCACAGGCUCCCACGUGGUGUCACAGAAGACCCAUUGGUGCUGGGUCUUGAAACAUGCAUAGGUUCCCGAAGGUGGGGACGUGGCUCUGCAGGAUGGGAAGAAGCCAUAGAGUGGACAGAAGUGGAGGUGGCAGAGUGAAGGGCUUGAACAGGGAAUGACAAGGGGCCUGCCUUAUCAGGAGGAAGGUGUUUGGGAGAAAGGCCAAGAAACAAUAUUGAGAGAAUGAGCCUGGAAAAGUGGGCCAGGGUGGGUCGUGAGGUGUGCUGGAUGCUACAUCAUGGAGCUUAGCCUCUGCUGGGCAGCAGUAGCUGGCCAAGGAAGGGAAGGAGUUGGAGAGUGACCAUCACACCAGGACUCCCUGGAGGGAAAGUUUCCUGGCUUCGGGGGAUGCGGUGCUUUGGAGAAAGAGACCCCAGAGUGGAGCUGGAUGGAGGAUGGAGACCAAAACAAGUGGAUGUGACCAGCAAGCCAGAGGACAAAGAUCUGCAAAGAGGUCGUGGCAGUGGGGGUCGAAAGGAGGGUUGGCAUUGGAGGAGCAGUGGCCCAUUGCCAUCCUGGAGGAAGCUGUCCCUUGGGAAGUGCUGAGAUCCCAGUGUUCGGAGCAGAAAACAUGUUGAGACUUAGUUGUAGACCAAGAGCUUGUCUGCCAGAGAAGAGAUGCAUGCUGGCUCCUGUGGGCUUUCAGUUGUGGGGCCAGAGAAAAGGAGGGCCACAUGUGUCAUGCUCUGCCGCUCUCUGGAACAGAGGUGCUUUCUGACAGGGCAGGCUGGGGGACAGUGAGCAGGGCCCUCACCCUCUCGUGGAGGUCCCCCGAGGGCCAGCUCCACACCCCCCACCACAUCUCAACGUGCAGGAGACUGGCUGCACCAUGACUGCUGGUUGCGAAGAAGUUAAAGGCCCCUGUCAACCCUCCGUGUUGAUUCUGAAAACAAAGCCAGAGUUCUUUCUGCAAAACGAAGCCUUUUUGUUUCUCUCUCUCUCUUUCAACAUUUCCCUGUUGUGUUAUGAAAAAGAGGUGGGUGGGGGACUUCAGAAGCUGUCUGGAGUGGCAGACAGCUCUGCAGGAUGAGCUGAGAGCGCCGCAGUCACACACAGGUGGGAGGAGAGGGCUGAGGGACAGUGGGCGCAGUGUCCCACCUCGUGGUGCGGUCAGUGGAGAAGGAGUCAUCGAUAAGGGGCCCCUGGCCAGGAGCCUCAGAUAUGGCUGCUGGGGAGCUUGACCCUCAAGGCUCUCAAGGAGAGGCUGGUGAGGAGACGUGGGGCCCUCUACUUCUGGUGCCAGGGAAGCCUCAGUAAGGGAGGUCGCUGCCUCUAGAGAAGGCUGCCUGGUUCCCAGCAAUGCUCAGCCAUCAAACUCCUCCAGAGGAGCUGUCCAUGGAGGGGUAGGUGUCAGCCCCCAUAUUUCUGCCACAACUAAGAGGAAGCUGGCUUCCUCAUCUUCACUGUAG